UUCUAUGUGUCCUCACAUGGUGGAGGAGGGGGCACACAGGUUCCCUUGUGACUCUUUUUUUUUUUUUUCUGAGACAAGGACUUUCUUGCUCUGUCACCCAGGCUGAAGUGCAGAGGCACAAUCCUAGCUCACUGCUUUCCUGGGUUUCUUGUACACAGAUCAGACCUAUGAGUGCAUGGUGGUCAUUACAGCUUCAACCUAUGCUAGAAGGCAGGCGUGAAGGAGGCUGCAGCUGCAGAUAUGGGAUGGUGGGAGGCUUCCCUGAGGAGGGGAUGUCGAAGGUGAGAGGUAGGAUGCGUGAGAUGCUUUCUGGGCAGUGGGAGAGGGUAUCCCAGUGUGCUGUGGGCUCUGGGGCUGCAGAGAUGCGUGUCUGUGGAGUUUGGAUAAGCCCCAUAAAAACACUCCACACAGUGCUUCUAGAAUCAGUCGGAGUCCAUGGCACAAAGCAAGGGCUCAGUAUAUACUGAGUGAAUGGAUGAAUGAAUGAAUGAGUGAAUGAAUGAAUGAGCCACCUGUCAAACUGCUUUCUCAGAUCAGUCCAGUCAGGGGAAUGGCGGUGGCCAUGGGCUUCUGUAGUGGAUGUCCUUAGGCUCGGUGUGGCUGGUGAUGAAGGACUGAGAGUCAUCCCAGAGAGUGCAGAACACCUCCCAUGACCUUCCCCAGAGUCCAAGCCCAGGGAGCAGUUGUGACAUCCAGCCAAGCUCACACUUGGCCUGGAGGCCGGACCCCAUGAGGACCAACCUGUGGUCUUCAGAGGUUGUCGGGAGGGAGGCCCCAGUGGACGCUGAAUUCCAGCCUCUGUCUGGAGGCCUUUGAGCAGCAAGCACCUGGUGGCUGCGCUGUGGAUGGGCUUGAUGGUCUGAACCCAUAACACCCAUUCAGGCAUCAGAAAAUCACCCUCGAAUUAUCUCUAGAGUUUUAUUUCCUAGAAUCCUGAAUAGAUCACAUUUUAUUGUUGAAUACUGAAAUCUCAUUACUUUAGGAAGUGCUAUUACUGGGCUAUUACUGGAAAGGAAUUCCUCUCUCCUGUUCUGAUUAAAACCUCCUGUUCAUAUUUAAAAAAUAAUUUCAGACCUUUUUUUUUAAUGCUUCUAAAAGUAUAAACGUGCAGCCAAGCGUCUUCUUUCCCUAGGCCCCGCGCCUGGGUGUGGACUUCCCUGGGCCUGCUGGUGGAGAGUGAGCGCAGCUCUGCAGAAGUAGAGACACCGGAGUCUCCUCCUGGACCCCCUUCUUGGAGAAUGAUCCCUUUCUUUUCCUCUGGCUCAGUUGCUUCCUAAGAUUCUAAUGACAGUUCUGGCCAAAACAGGCAGCCCCCGUUACCACUGGUUUGAGACUUCAGCUCUGGCUUUUUUCACCAGGAACUGAUUCUGGGAUCUUGGGGCAUAGGGUCCAAGAUAUGGCUUCUCUGCUGACUGAUGGAGUCAGGGGAGCUGGUUCCACCCAGAGCAAUACGUGGGGAUGGGUGGAAAGCACUCCUCCGGGCAGCUCCUGCUCCUCUCUGGAGGCUGCUCCCUCCGCGCACAGGGUCAUCAGCUUCCUGCGUCUGAAUCCCCAACCUGGGGGUGUCCUCUAUGGCCCUCUGGGCUCACUUGGCACUAUCACAUGCCGAGCCCACUGUGUCAUGAAUAUUACCUGGUGACUUGCUCCUUUCUCCUCCUCUGGGACUCUGCCCGUUCUCUGUGACCCCAAUGUACUUGGCACAGGGACUGGCAUGGGGCACUCAGAAAAUAUUUGUCAAAUGGAUGGUGGAAUUCACCAGCACCCAGAAAGCAGUGUGAUUUGGGGAGUUUUAUCAGCGAGUGGCCAUGUGACUCCCAGGGGCAGAGGGGAUGUCUUCAGCACAUCUCCGUCCCUUUGCCAAUCACACCCUGCUCAGUAGAGCCCACCUUGCCUGUCCUCCUCAUUGCCUGCCCUGUUCUUGCCUGGCCGCACUGAGCUCCACAUGAGGUAUAUUCCACAUGGACACAGGGGAGGUGACCCCCUUCUCUCCAGGGCUGCUCCUCCAAGGCCGCGGGUUGCCUUGGAGAAAGCUCAGAAUAGCUGUGUGGCCCCAUGCUGAUGCUGGGUGAGUGUGCAUGUGGCUAGAAUUCUUUUCUGGACUCUUGGCAAAUGGAAUUAUUUACAACCACCAGGGCCAAUAUUUCCCUGCUCCGCAGAUGAUUUGCAGCAGAUGAAGUAGAUGCUCUCUCCUUGCAGAGAGCUAAUGAUAACAUUGAGCUCUUCCCACCCCACUGAUGUGUCUUUGAUGGCACAGCUGUGGAUAUUUUUAUUUGCCCAGUCAAGUCGGCUCCUCGGUGCACAUGUCUGAAGUGAAGGCCCUUGGGCUGCAAGCUGCAGAGGGCACUGGCGCCAGCCUUGUGCGUUGACAGGAGACUGCAGGAACCCGCCAGCUUGGUUGCUGGCUUCCUGAGCUCUGUCUGUGGGUUCCCUCCCUGGAAUGGACAAGGGGGAGCAGCCGAUUUCUGAUACAGCUCAUCUGUCUGGGUCACUGGUUCCAGAAGUUAAUUUUGGAUGGAACUUCACAGGCACCUGGCGUCUGGUUAUGCAAAACCUGACCUUUGGCUUCACUCUGGGGCCUUCCCUUCUCCUCACCCCAGGGCUCCUGCUGCCUCCCUCUCUGUGCCAUUCUUUCCUCUUAAAAAAAAAUAUCCUGCUGACAGGAGCUUUCUAACUUGUCAUUUUGGAGAUCAUCAACAAAUUCUAUAGAGAGGUGACCUCCAUUAUGAGAAAGAGACGGGGAGUUGGCUGGGACCCAAGCCAAGGAGCUGGAGCCUCUUUUGACUGGCAAGGUGACAUUGAGUGUCAUAUCAGCAUUCAUGGCCAGCUCUCUUCUCCUCAGAGAGUAAUUAUUUCUUUCAGAGCGAAAGGUCCAAUUUGCUGUAAAGAACAGAGCCCCAGGUAAAACGAAAGAGCUAUAAGCUCCCCUGACAUAAAGGAGACCAGACUGCCCCCGUCCCCAGCCCUGCUCACUCCACAUCAUAAUGGCCAUUUGGCCAGAUUUAUUAUGUUUACUUGUACUUCCUUCCUGUCAUAACACAUUAGGGUGGUUGCACAUUGCAUGGGUGAGGCCGGCUCAGCAGGUGGAGCUGAACACCUUGCAGCUGACACUGGCUCUUGUAUCCUUGGCCAGCACCUGGCUCUGGGCAGGGAUUGAGAUGGCACCUUUGGAGAAACACUGGGAGAGCUGAUGCCUGGCAUUUGGGGCCAAGCUGAGCUCUGGGCCCUCUGCACUCUCCUGGUAUUUCCUCUACUCCUGGGACAUUACAAGAAUAAGUGGCCUAAGUCUGUGGCCUUGGAUGCCAAUACCACGAUAGAUGUCAUUCACUGAGUGCUCACCCUGACCCAGAUCAUGAGACACUGGGCACUGAUGGUUUUAUUUAGCACAGGCCCUGGGCACUCAUGGUUUCACUGGGCACAGGCCCUGGGCACUCAUGGUUUCACUGGGCACAGGCCCUGGGCACUCAUGGUUUCGUUGGGCACAGACACUGGGCACUCAUGGUUUCGUUGGGCACAGACACUGGGCACUUAUGGUUUCACUGGGUGCAGGCACUGGGCAUGGAUGGUUUCAUUGGGUGCAUGCCCUGAGCACUCAUGGUUUCACUGGGCACAGGCCCUGGGCACUCAUGGUUUCACUGGGUGCAGGCCCUGGGCACUCAUGGUUUCAUUGGGCGCAGACAUUGGGCACUCAUGGUUUCACUGGGCGCAGGCACUGGGCACUUAUGGUUUCAUUGGGUGCAGGCGCUGGGCAUGGAUGGUUUCAUUGGGUGCAGGCCCUGGGCAUGGAUGGUUUCAUUGGGCACAGACACUGGGCACUCAUGGUUUCAUUGGGUGCAGGCACUGGGCAUGGAUGGUUUCAUUGGGUGUAUGCCCUGGGCACUCAUGGUUUCACUGGGCACAGGCCCUGGGCACUCAUGGUUUCAUUGGGCGCAGACACUGGGCACUUAUUGUUUCAUUGGGUGCAGACACUGGGCAUGGAUGGUUUCAUUGGGUGCAGGCCCUGGGCACUCAUGCUUUCAUUGGGCGCAGGCACUGGGCACUCAUGGUUUCAUUGGGCGCAGGCACUGGGCACUCAUGGUUUCACUGGGUGCAGAUACCUAGCACACAAAGCAGUCCUAUUUGCCCAUCUAUGGCUGAGCAGAGUGAGCUCACAGUCAGUGACCCCUUCCCAGGCCCCACCCCCACUAGCACAGGAGUUCCCGCUGUGUGCACCCAUGGCGUGGCUCUGGGGUGGCUCUGGGUGGCCCUCAUCACUUGGACUGCCUUUUCUUCUUUUCUCGUCUGCCCUCCCCUAAGCUGUAGCUCCAUUUCUGUCUUGCACGCUGCUGCAGCUUCAGCACCCACCGUGGUACCUGGCUCGCUGUGGUGUUCCGCACAUGUUGUUAAAUUUAAAUUGUUAAAUGAUUGGAUGAGCCUGACGUGAGAUGAGGACCUGCCCAGAGUCAUCCAGCUGCUCAUCCACAGAGCCUGGGCUGUCCUGCCACGAAGCCCUUGCCAGUCACUAUGCCUUCUUGACUUCCCAUGGCACCAUGACUGUCACACUGCACUGUGGCACAGUGUACCUCCACCUUCCUCCUUCUGCUUCUGUUUUUGGGAGUUCAGUCAAAGCUGACAUGUUGCCCAAGACUAGAGGGGAGAGUUUGGAGGCCGGAGAGGAUGGCCAGGUCCUGGGUGUGGAGGUUGCUUCCUGCCCCUCCUCCUCCCCCACCACAGGGGCCUGGAGAAGGUAGGGUGGUGUCCUCAGUGAGGAUGGUCUGAAGGGGGCCCAGGAGCAGAGGGAGGAGUCAUGGUUGGUUGGAAAUUAGGACAACCAAUGCAGGAAGCUCUCUGUCACAGCUUGCCCAUUCUGUAGGUGAGAUCCGUGAAGGUCAGGAAGUUGAAUAACCUACCUAAGUUUAUCUGGCUACUUAGGGGAAGAACAGAGUUCAGACUUGAACUUGAGGUGCCCUAAUGAGUGUAAGAGUUUGAGGGGGUCAUUCACAAGCAUACCCUCGCUUCUGACACUAAGUGUAAAUUCAGGGCAGGACCACUCUGUGGUUCCAUAAUUCACUGAAGGACUCACAGAACUUGCUGAAAUCUGUUAUGCGUGUGGUUAAGGCUUAUCAGAGUGAAAGGACACAGAUUAAAAUCAGCUGAGGGAAGAGACACAUGGGGUAGGGUGCAGACAGGUUCUGGGUGGGGAUUCCAGCCAUCCUCUAUGGGUAAGUUGUGGGACCACUAGCGUCUCCCCACAGCCUGUGUGUCGGUGUCGCCAACCAGGAAGCUCGCUGGGCCUUGGUGCCCAGUCUUUACUGGGGCUCACACAUAGACCUGGUUAGCUACCCACAUGUCUUCAGCCUCCAGCCCUGCCUAGGACAAGCUGAGGUCAUGGGACCCCAAACACACCCCCUUAUCACAUUGUUAGACUCUCGAGCAUGGCCCAAAGCUCCAAAGACACUCUCACCUGAUCAGUCCCCUCCUAGGAGCCCAGGGCACAGCCCAGACCUCUCUGUGGGUAAGGUUAAUUCUUGAUUGAAUAGAGUACUAUGUAGGAGAGUGUCUAGGAACUAAAUUCGGGCUUAUUCCCUGAUAGACUCUUCUCACCCCGGGUCAAGGUACUUCAGGCCCUUGCCAUGGCCCACUGGUGACGUGGGUCCCUGCUGCGGCGUUCAGGCCCCUUGCUUACAUCACGGCACUUCUCUCUUUUCCAGACUGACAGCAGCAAUCACAGUCACAUUCCACAGCCUCUCCAGCACCCAGCCAGCUCUCCGCGGGGGCAGCAGGGACUGGUCCACCCAACAACAGCAGCCAUGUCCUCACCUCUUGCUACAGCAGCAACUUUAUUUGAUUUGAUGUAUAUGAAGAAAUAAAACUCAGAAGUCAAUUGACUUAAACAUGGAA